CAUUAGACCCGGUCCAAUUGCUGGGGCUGCAGCGCUGCCUCCGAGACCGCGAGGUGGGUGGAUCGGGUCUUCCUGGAAGGGUGCGAUAAGGCCGGGCGAGGUGCCUGGGAUGCUUCUCCCCUUCCGCGAGGAAGAGAUCUAAUUGGGUAGGGCGGGUGUAGACUAGCCUGCCGAGCCGCCCGCUGGCACCUGCAGCCUCCUGGGCGCCCGCCGGGCCCCGGCGAGAAAGUUGUUAAAGGGAGCGAGGUGGUUGUUCCUGGGGUCCGAGGCGCGCCUCUCACGCCCUGCCCAACAGAAGCCGCAGUCCCGUGGGGUCUGGAGACGCAGUUUCCUGUUAAUGACAAUAAAUCCCUGCUCCCCCUGCCUCAGACAUCUACGCAGCGAAAUCGAGCCUGGCCUUGAGGGUCCACACCGCGAGGGAAGAUGCGUGCGCCCAUUCCAGAGCCUAAGCCUGGAGACCUGAUUGAGAUUUUUCGCCCUUUCUACAGACACUGGGCCAUCUAUGUUGGCGAUGGAUAUGUGGUUCAUCUGGCCCCUCCAAGUGAGGUCGCAGGAGCUGGUGCAGCCAGUGUCAUGUCCGCCCUGACUGACAAGGCCAUCGUGAAGAAGGAAUUGCUGUAUGAUGUGGCCGGGAGUGACAAGUACCAGGUCAACAACAAACAUGAUGACAAGUACUCGCCGCUGCCCUGCAGCAAAAUCAUCCAGCGGGCGGAGGAGCUGGUGGGGCAGGAGGUGCUCUACAAGCUGACCAGUGAGAACUGCGAGCACUUUGUGAAUGAGCUGCGCUAUGGAGUCGCCCGCAGUGACCAGGUCAGAGAUGUCAUCAUCGCUGCAAGCGUUGCAGGAAUGGGCUUGGCAGCCAUGAGCCUUAUUGGAGUCAUGUUCUCAAGAAACAAGCGACAAAAGCAAUAACUGAAAAAGACUGUCCUGUCAGCGAUGACUUUAUACAUCAAGGGGGUCUUGUUUUGCUAGAGAGUUUGGGGUUUGGUUUGUGGAUUUCAUUGUGAUUUAUAAUAAGGCUUAUUUUCACAGAAUAAAAUAAAGCAAAACGAGGGAGGAUUUUAUUGGGGGAAGUGCAGCAAGAACUGCCUGGUGUGAAGUCUGUUCAGGGAACAGCCGGGCUGUCUUCCUGGUCAGGGAUUGUCUUUCACUUUCUUUUUGCGUGCUGUGUUCUUUGCAUUGCAGGAGGCAGAGUCCAGCUCCAGUUAUCUCAAGUAGAGGGCGUUUCUGGUCGUCAGGAUACAUGCGGGGCGGAAGGGAGACAGAAAGACAUAAUACACAAGAACAGAAAGCAGCAGACAGCCAGGACCCUUGGCCCGGAACUAGAUCUAGGAUGGCCUCUGAGACUCAGCAGCUGGAGUCUGUAGAUGUUCAGCUGAGUUGAAAAAAAAAAAG